CAAAGUGAGGAAGCUGUCUCCAUAGGGAAGAGGCCUGAUGUGGACUGUCCGAACUGAAGGAGGGCACUUUCCUCUCCAUAGCCCCACCUUCUCCUGGAGGAAUGUAGCUUUCCUGCUGCUUCUCUCCCUUGCUUUGGAGUGGACUUCUGCAAUGCUGACCAAGAAGAUCAAACACAAACCAGGGUUAUGUCCCAAAGAGAGGCUCACCUGUACCACUGAACUUCCGGACUCAUGUAACACAGAUUUUGACUGCAAGGAAUACCAGAAGUGCUGCUUUUUUGCCUGUCAGAAGAAGUGCAUGGAUCCCUUUCAAGAACCCUGCAUGCUACCUGUGAGGCAUGGAAACUGUAAUCAUGAGGCACAGCGCUGGCAUUUUGACUUUAAAAAUUACCGCUGCACACCCUUCAAAUACAGGGGCUGCGAAGGGAAUGCCAACAACUUCUUAAAUGAGGAUGCCUGCAGAACGGCCUGCAUGUUAAUUGUUAAGGAUGGACAAUGCCCACUCUUCCCUUUCACUGAACGUAAGGAGUGUCCACCUUCAUGUCACAGUGACAUCGAUUGUCCCCAGACAGACAAAUGUUGUGAAUCCAGGUGUGGCUUUGUUUGUGCCAGGGCCUGGACAGGUAAGGAUUGGGGAUAUACCUCCCAAAUCUAUUGGGCAUGUGCCAAGGAUGUCAUGCUGUCUCCAUGGAGUGGGGGGUGUCUUGAACCUCAGAUGCUCCUUGGGCUCAUCUUUGAGGAUCUUUGGGAACCCCUUUUAAUGCCCAACAAGUUAUAUUGACCUCUUGACCUCUGAAGACUAUUGUGCUGUUCUUCAAAGCCAGUAAUUCAUAGCAUUGCUCUCUAUUCUUCCCCAAGAAAACUUAUUUUUUCUGAGACUCAUUCCUCAAUGACUUGCAAGGUGACAAUAUUCACCGAUUCAUAAAAAAUUCAUAACCAUGAGGUGUAUUCCUAAUAAGCCCUCAUGUCUGCACAGAACUUCAAAGCAUGCACAUCAUAUUCAUAUCCUGUAAGAUGGGCUGGGGAAAACAUUAGUAGCAAAUGAUGUUGGAUAGAAGCCAACUUUCCUGCCUCCUCUAAGGCAGGUGUUUACUUCCCCAUGUAGUCCCAGGGAUUGUCCAGGUGUGGCUUUAAGGUUCUAAGGUUCAGUAUAGUGUGGUGGCAGGAGUCCAAGGCUUUUCAACCUACUUCAACUUUUCUACUGGCUUUCUAUGUGGCAUUGGGCAACUCAUUUCCCUCUAAAUACGCCUCAAUGCCUACAAUUUGUAAAACAAGAAGGUUCUGUGUGCUAAUACUCCUGCCACCUGUGGUACUCUGGGGUUAUAUAACCCAGAUCCAUUAAUUCUGUAGGAGCAGACAGGAAUCCUAUCAGAUGGUACAAGUCAGAGAUGGUAAGACUUUUCUUGAUGCUCCUCAAGUUAUUAGUCGUAGAAAGUUGAUACUCUGCCUCCUCCAGUCUAUUGUUACUGUAGGGGGAAAGGUAAGAAGCUUAAUCAGAAUAAAACCUUGUUUGAGAUUCCCAAGAUUCCUCAAAUUUGUCUCAAAUUAUGACCAAGUAUUUCAAGGUCAAGUGUUUUCUUUUACCCCAUAAAGUCAAAAAAGGUUUCUGCCCACGCAAGCCCUUGCUAUGUACCAAGAUUGAUAAACCCAAGUGCCUGCAGGAUGAGGAG